AAUGUGUAUGUAGAGCUAUGUAUACCGCUCCACACCCUUUCGUGCCCGCGCGCUGAAGGUUCUGGGGUUCGUAUCCGCGCGCUUGCGCUGCAAGACUCGGCAAGUUUGUUCCGACUGUAACUCCGGGGAUGAGGAACGGGGUCUCUCGCCCCUCCUCCGGCUUCGCAGCCCCCGACCCCAAGUGGGCUCCCCGCCCACAGCAGUGUUCGUCCUCCUACCUCCUGGCCCCCUCCCUUCCGCUGGGAUUUGGAUCUAACCAAUGAAGCUCCUCUGUCAUCAGGUUGUGCGAGGACCUGUUUGUACCCAGAGUCAAGAAUGGAGUUGACUUACUUCCAGAGGUUGACUGCUUUAGCACCAAUGAACCCAGCAACAUGUCAUACGUGAAAGAGACAGUGGACAGAUUGCUCAAAGGAUAUGACAUUCGCUUGCGGCCGGACUUCGGAGGGCCCCCCGUCGACGUUGGGAUGCGGAUCGAUGUCGCCAGCAUAGACAUGGUCUCCGAAGUGAAUAUGGAUUAUACACUCACCAUGUAUUUCCAGCAGUCUUGGAAAGACAAAAGGCUUUCUUAUUCUGGAAUCCCACUGAACCUCACCCUAGACAAUAGGGUAGCUGACCAACUCUGGGUACCAGACACCUACUUUCUGAAUGACAAGAAAUCAUUUGUGCAUGGGGUCACAGUGAAAAAUCGAAUGAUUCGACUGCAUCCUGAUGGAACAGUUCUCUAUGGACUCCGAAUCACAACCACAGCUGCAUGUAUGAUGGAUCUUCGAAGAUAUCCAUUGGAUGAGCAGAACUGCACCCUGGAGAUCGAAAGUUAUGGCUAUACCACUGAUGACAUUGAAUUUUACUGGAAUGGAGGAGAAGGGGCAGUCACUGGUGUUAAUAAAAUCGAACUUCCUCAAUUUUCAAUUGUUGACUACAAGAUGGUGUCUAAGAAGGUGGAGUUCACAACAGGAGCGUAUCCACGACUGUCACUAAGUUUUCGUCUAAAGAGAAACAUUGGUUACUUCAUUUUGCAAACCUACAUGCCUUCUACACUGAUUACAAUUCUGUCCUGGGUGUCUUUUUGGAUCAACUAUGAUGCAUCUGCAGCCAGAGUCGCACUAGGAAUCACGACAGUGCUUACAAUGACAACCAUCAGCACCCACCUCAGGGAGACCCUGCCAAAGAUCCCUUAUGUCAAAGCGAUUGAUAUUUAUCUGAUGGGUUGCUUUGUGUUUGUGUUCCUGGCUCUGCUGGAGUAUGCCUUUGUAAAUUACAUCUUCUUUGGGAAAGGCCCUCAGAAAAAGGGAGCUAGCAAACAAGACCAGAGUGCCAAUGAGAAGAAUAAACUGGAGAUGAAUAAAGUCCAGGUCGACGCCCACGGUAACAUUCUCCUCAGCACCCUGGAAAUCCGGAAUGAGACGAGUGGCUCGGAAGUGCUCACGAGCGUGAGCGACCCCAAGGCCACCAUGUACUCCUAUGACAGCGCCAGCAUCCAGUACCGCAAGCCCCUGAGCAGCCGCGAGGCCUACGGGCGCGCCCUGGACCGGCACGGGGUACCCAGCAAGGGGCGCAUCCGCAGGCGUGCCUCCCAGCUCAAAGUCAAGAUCCCCGACUUGACUGAUGUGAAUUCCAUAGACAAGUGGUCCCGAAUGUUUUUCCCCAUCACCUUUUCUCUUUUUAAUGUCGUCUAUUGGCUUUACUAUGUACACUGAGGUCUGUUCUAAUGGUUCCAUUUAGACUACUUUCCUCUUCUAUUGUUUUUUAACCUUACAGGUCCCCAACAGCGAUACUGCUGUUUCUCGAGGUAAGAGAUUCAGCCAUCCAAUUGGUUUUAGGUCUUGCAUAUCAGUUUUAUUACUGCACCAUGUUUACUUCAAAAAGACAAAACAAAAAAAAAAUUAUUUUUCCAGUCUACCGUGGUCCAGGUUAUCAGCUCUUUAAGAGCUCUAUUAAUUGCCAUGUUUACAAACAAACACAAAGAGAGAAGUUAGACAGGUAGAUCUUUAGCAGUCUUUUCUAGUUUCCCUGGAUUUCACUGAUUUAUUUUUUAGGGAAAAUGAAAAGAGGACCUUGCUGUCCGCCUGCACUGCUUCCUGGUAAACUAUAACAAACUUAUGCUGCCAAAAAAAAAAAAAAAAAAA